AGUUGGCAAGCGGACCACCAGCAACAGACAACAUCUUCAUUCGGCUCUCCCUGAAGCUGUACUGCCUCGCUGAGAGGAUGAAGGUCUCCGAGGCUGCCCUGUCUCUCCUUGUCCUCAUCCUUAUCAUUACUUCGGCUUCUCGCAGCCAGCCAAAAGUUCCUGAGUGGGUGAACACCCCAUCCACCUGCUGCCUGAAGUAUUAUGAGAAAGUGUUGCCAAGGAGACUAGUGGUGGGAUACAGAAAGGCCCUCAACUGUCACCUGCCAGCAAUCAUCUUCGUCACCAAGAGGAACCGAGAAGUCUGCACCAACCCCAAUGACGACUGGGUCCAAGAGUACAUCAAGGAUCCCAACCUACCUUUGCUGCCUACCAGGAACUUGUCCACGGUUAAAAUUAUUACAGCAAAGAAUGGUCAACCCCAGCUCCUCAACUCCCAGUGAUGACCAGGCUUUAGUGGAAGCCCUUGUUUACAGAAGAGAGGGGUAAACCUAUGAAAACAGGGGAAGCCUUAUUAGGCUGAAACUAGCCAGUCACAUUGAGAGAAGCAGAACAAUGAUCAAAAUAAAGGAGAAGUAUUUCGAAUAUUUUCUCAAUCUUAGGAGGAAAUACCAAAGUUAAGGGACGUGGGCAGAGGUACGCUCUUUUAUUUUUAUAUUUAUAUUUUUAUUUUUUUGAGAUAGGGUCUUACUCUGUCACCCAGGCUGGAGUGCAGUGGUGUGAUCUUGGCUCACUUGAUCUUGGCUCACUGUAACCUCCACCUCCCAGGCUCAAGUGAUCCUCCCACCCCAGCCUCCCGAGUAGCUGGGACUACAGGCUUGCGCCACCACACCUGGCUAAUUUUUGUAUUUUUGGUAGAGACGGGAUUCUACCAUGUUGCCCAGGCUGGUCUCAAACUCGUGUGCCCAAGCAAUCCACCUGCCUCAGCCUUCCAAAAGUGCUGGGAUUACAGGCGUGAGCCACCACAUCCGGCCAGUGCACUCUUAAUACACAGAAAAAUAUAUUUCACAUCCUUCUCCUGCUCUCUUUCAAUUCCUCACUUCACACCAGUACACAAGCCAUUCUAAAUACUUAGCCAGUUUCCAGCCUUCCAGAUGAUCUUUGCCCUCUGGGUCUUGACCCAUUAAGAGCCCCAUAGAACUCUUGAUUUUUCCUGUCCAUCUUUAUGGAUUUUUCUGGAUCUAUAUUUUCUUCAAUUAUUCUUUCAUUUUAUAAUGCAACUUUUUCAUAGGAAGUCCGGAUGGGAAUAUUCACAUUAAUCAUUUUUGCAGAGACUUUGCUAGAUCCUCUCAUAUUUUGUCUUCCUCAGGGUGGCAGGGGUACAGAGAGUGCCUGAUUGGAAAAAAAAAAAAAAGAGAGAGAGAGAGAAGAAGAAGAAGAAGAGACACAAAUCUCUACCUCCCAUGUUAAGCUUUGCAGGACAGGGAAAGAAAGGGUAUGAGACACGGCUAGGGGUAAACUCUUAGUCCAAAACCCAAACAUGCAAUAAAUAAAACUCCCUUAUUUGACA